GUCGGCCAUUUUGUGUCUGCUUCCUGUGGGACGUGGUGGUAGCCGUUGGGUUGGGAAAGUGAGGGAUUUUUGGCCUCGUUUCUCCUGCUUCUUUUCUCCUCCCUUUUACUUUGCCGGUAGAACACAGUUAUGGGUCGCAAGAAGAAGAAGCAGCUGAAGCCGUGGUGCUGGUAUUGUAAUAGAGAUUUUGAUGAUGAGAAGAUCCUUAUUCAGCACCAAAAAGCAAAGCAUUUUAAAUGCCAUAUAUGUCACAAGAAAUUGUAUACAGGACCUGGCUUAGCUAUUCAUUGCAUGCAGGUACAUAAAGAAACAAUAGAUGCCGUACCAAAUGCAAUACCUGGAAGAACAGACAUAGAGUUGGAAAUAUAUGGUAUGGAAGGUAUUCCAGAAAAAGACAUGGAUGAAAGACGACGACUUCUUGAACAGAAAACACAAGAAAGUCAAAAAAAGAAGCAACAAGAUGAUUCUGAUGAAUAUGAUGAUGACGACUCUGCAGCCUCAACUUCAUUUCAGCCACAGCCUGUUCAACCUCAGCAAGGUUAUAUUCCUCCAAUGGCACAGCCAGGACUGCCACCAGUACCAGGAGCACCAGGAAUGCCUCCAGGCAUACCUCCAUUAAUGCCAGGUGUUCCUCCUCUGAUGCCAGGAAUGCCACCAGUUAUGCCAGGCAUGCCACCUGGAUUGCAUCAUCAGAGAAAAUACACCCAGUCAUUUUGCGGUGAAAACAUAAUGAUGCCAAUGGGUGGAAUGAUGCCACCUGGACCAGGAAUACCACCUCUGAUGCCUGGAAUGCCACCAGGUAUGCCCCCACCUGUUCCACGUCCUGGAAUUCCUCCAAUGACUCAAGCACAGGCUGUUUCAGCGCCAGGUAUUCUUAAUAGACCACCUGCACCAACAGCAACUGUACCUGCCCCACAGCCUCCAGUUACUAAGCCUCUUUUCCCCAGUGCUGGACAGAUGGGGACACCUGUCACAAGCUCAAGUACAGCUUCAUCCAAUUCAGAAAGUCUGUCUGCAUCUUCUAAAGCUCUGUUUCCUAGCACAGCACAAGCUCAGGCAGCUGUCCAAGGACCUGUUGGUACAGAUUUCAAACCCUUAAAUAGUACCCCUGCAACAACUACAGAACCCCCAAAGCCUACAUUCCCUGCUUAUACACAGUCUACAGCUUCAACAACUAGUACAACAAAUAGUACUGCAGCUAAACCAGCGGCUUCAAUAACAAGUAAGCCUGCUACACUUACAACAACUAGUGCAACCAGUAAGUUGAUCCAUCCAGAUGAGGAUAUAUCCCUGGAAGAGAGAAGGGCACAGUUACCUAAGUAUCAACGUAAUCUUCCUCGGCCAGGACAGGCCCCCAUCGGUAAUCCACCAGUUGGACCAAUUGGAGGUAUGAUGCCACCACAGCCAGGCAUCCCACAGCAACAAGGAAUGAGACCCCCAAUGCCACCUCAUGGUCAGUAUGGUGGUCAUCAUCAAGGCAUGCCAGGAUACCUUCCUGGUGCUAUGCCCCCGUAUGGGCAGGGACCGCCAAUGGUGCCCCCUUACCAGGGUGGGCCUCCUCGACCUCCGAUGGGAAUGAGACCUCCUGUAAUGUCGCAAGGUGGCCGUUACUGAUCUUACUUCAUCCAGUCUAAUAGGUUUGGAGAUUAAACCUUUUCUCAACUUGUGCUGUUUAUAUAGCCAAGCUUCCGUCAAUAAGGCUUCAUUGUGACUUUAACAAACAUUAUCUUCCCACAUACCAGGAACUAUUGGACAUUUAUUUUACAUGGGAAAAAUUAUUUGGAAUAAUAAAGCAGGAACUUUUCCUGAAGUUGCAAUUUAUACUGUAUGGCUUCUUUUUCAUGUUUCAUCUAGGUUUUUAGAAGUGAAGUAUAGUAAAUUUGGUUCGUUAAAUUGUGAAGGCGCUGGAAUUACAUGAACAUACCACCCUAGUAAAGGCAAGUUCUGUAAGCUUACAUUGCUAUUUGUAAAGUUUGCCUUCACAGCAUUUCAGAUGCUGUUGGACUUCAUGUCCCCAACCUAGCUUGGUGAGGGCUGUAACUGUUUCCAAGUACUUGUACAUUGGAAGUCUGAAUGUGUAACAAUAUUUAAUGUAUUUAGAGUUCCUCAUGUUGCAGGGUUUAAGAAAUCUGACCCACCAAGGUCAUGUGACUUUUCUGUACUGUUAAACUUCAUUGUAAUAAAAUGAGAGAAAAAUUUAUGCCUUUUUAUUCAUAACCCAGCUGUGGACCACUGCCUGAAAGGUUUGUACAGAUGCAUGCCACAGUAGAUGUCCACAUAAUAAAAUUCAUAGUUACCAAUGCAGUUUUGAUAUAUCAUUGGAUUCUGUCUUUGAGUUGUAGGUUAUUUCUUAGCUGCAUGUUUUAAACUGAAUUUGCAUAGAGUUGUAUGUUAAUGUUUCAGUUAAGAGAAAAACUUAAGAUACAUGAGUCAUUACAUAAUGGGUAUGAAAUCUUUAUAAUCACCCUUCCACCCUCUAUGGUGUCAGUACACAUCACGUGUCAUAGAUACUUAAAAUGUAAAUGUUAACACUUUUCCUUCCUGCUGAGAUGUUUAGAGCCUAGUGCCAGACCCAUUCAUUUCCUUUUGAUUAUUUUUGAGACUCAGUACUGCAUGGACCUCAGAAGCUUUUCAGGUGCAAACUUCUAGAAGCUUAGGUGCAUGCAGUAAUAGCUUCUUGUGCUGUUAAUGGGUUAUUAUAUAUUAUUCUAAGUGUAAUGCUGAGAAUCUAAAUGUGUCUCUGUUGGGAUGGUUAACAGAUGAAUUGGCAAUUUUUAUUAUGUUCCUGGAAGAUUACAUUAUUCAUUUGAGUACCUUCUGUUAUUAAGCCUAGGUAGCCUUACUGUGCAACUUUUUAUUUAUCCUUGGAAAUUUUGAAUGUUGUGUUCUUACAGAGAGCUUUUCUGUAGAGAUGACUGCUAUUCAAUAUUUUGUGUUGCAACCUCUUAAAAUAAUAGCUCUUGUUGACCUUUUUGGGAUCUGUUUUUCUGAUCUUUUGCAGGGUAGUUUUAUGAUUUUUUAGGCAUCAAAUAACCUAUGCAAAGUAUUAAUAUAAUGAACUCAAGUUGAGUUUUUCUCAUUAUAAAGUUAAGACUUCUAAGAAAAUGGUAACAUUUCUUUAUAACUUUCCUGUGAAGGUAUAGAUAAAACACAUGAAGUCUGAAGUUGUAUGGAAAAAAGGGCUUUAACUUUGAAGGAAAAUAUAUUGAAAAGUGAUUUAGCCAUCACAAAAGAGUUCGUAUUUAUGUGACAGAUGAAAGUCAUACCUUUAAGCAAAACAUUGCAAGUAUUAUAAAGCUGAAUGCUAUUUUAACUCACAUUGGCUGGGUGCAGUGGCUCACGCCUGUAAUCCCAGCCCUCUGGAAGGCUGAGAUGGGAGGAUUGCUUGAGUCCAGGAGUUUGAGACCAGCCUGGCCAACAUGGCAAAACCCCAUCUGUACAAAACAUUUAAAAAUUAGCCAGGCGCGUUAGUGUGUGUCUGUGGUCCCAGCUGCUCAAGAGGCUGAGGAAGGAGGUUCUUCCUCCUUCCGAGGCUGCGGUGAGCUAUGUUCACUCCAGCCUGGGCAACAGAGCGAGACUCUGUCAAAAAAUAAAUUAAAAUAUCUGAUUAUCUGGCUUCAAUGAUUUUGGCUCCUGUGCUUGUGGUACCAUAGUGGUACAAAAAUUUUCAUAGUUUGAAAAUAAAACAGGUAUUUUGCCAGUAAUGUAUUUCUUUCUGCCAGCAGCCAAGUCCCAAACCACUUUCCCCUCUGAACCUCUGCUUACCUAAAUGGUUUCAAAAUUAAUACAUGCUGCUUUGAUUUGGCAGCACACUUAAUAUACUGCUGAAGGAAAACUUGUGUUGAAAGUCUUUAAGAUAAAAAUGGUGUGAUAGGCCGGGCGCAGUGGCUCACGCCUGUAAUCCCAGCACUUUGGGAGGCCCAGGCGGGUGGAUCAUGAGGUCAGGAGAUGGAGACCAUCCUGGCUAACACGGUGAAACCCCGUUUCUACUAAAAAUACAAAAAAUUAGCUGGGCGUAGUUGCGGAUGCCUGUAGUCCCAACUACUCUGGAGACCGAGGCAGGAGAAUGGCGUGAACCCGGGAGGCAUAGCUUGCAGUGAGCGGAGAUCACACCACUGCACUCUAGCCUGGACGACAGAUUGAGACUCCGUCUCAAAAAAAAAAAAUGCUGUGAUUAAAUUUAGAAUAAUUAAGUAAGGGGUGCUCUCCCAAAUUCUCAGGAAUUUCAUGUAUACGGUUAUUGACAAACUGCAAUAGGGUUAGUAGACCUGUUUCAGAAAUUAUGUGAAGCUUUAUUUGCAUUUUAUGCAAAGAAGGUUGAUACUUUGUAGCAAGGUUUUUUGCUCUCUGUAUAGGUCUGAUGGGCAAAAAUGGAACUUUUAAAUAUGGGAUAGAAUUCUAAUUAAAAAUUAAUUGAAAGUGUUAGGCAUUGGCAGAUAAAACUUAAGCUCAUGAGUUCCUGAGUUUGUAGCUAUAGGCUCAGAGGUGGUGUACCCAUUUAAUAUAUUUGAAGUGUAAUUUUUGCAUGCAUCCAAACGUAAUUAAGCUUCUAGAAAAUACCUUUUUUCUAAAUGCUUCUGGGGUCCAUAGUGUGGUUGAAUUAUGAGUGGAGCAAAUUAUAUUCAUAUAAUUAACUCUGACUCAACCUUCCUUAAGUAGUAGAUGAAGUUGAGUCAAAGUGGAUGCCAACUGCCCUCACAGAAGACAACUUUUGGGACUUGAUAAUUCAGGCAGGCAUUGUGAUUGUCAUAAUUAAGGAAGCUGUAAGGUUAGUAGGGCUGGCAACUUUGGCUCUACCUUACAUCCACCCCUUUUAGAAAAACAAGAAAACAUUUUGUCUGGCACUAGUUUCUGUUGUAUAAGUUUUCAUACUGUUUAACAAGACCACAGCAGGUAAGGAUUAAUUUUUGAGUGGCUGCUGGAAUUACUUGAUUUGAAUACUUAGUAUUUUAGUAGUGUCUCACACAUUUGCCAUUAGGUAUGAAUAAAAUAUUCCUACUGUACUCCUAUUCCACUAAGUUACAUUUUGAACUUAGACUCACCUUAAUUAAACUUAAUUAAUUGGGGAGGGGGAUUCCCCAACAAAAAGAAGUACGGGCUCAGAGUGGAAUUGUAGUGGACAAUAGUUAAAAACAAAGCUGCUCCUUUUGCUUGCUUGAUCAUUGGGAUUUUUAAAAAAAAAAAUUUUAAUGCAUGUCUUUUAAAUUAAUUGGGAACUGUUUUUCUAAAAUUAAAAUUUUCUUCUUCCUAUAGCCCUGCCAUAGGACAGGCUGAGGCUGAGUCUCAGUGUUGCCCUGUUCAGUCUGAGGCAAGUGGGAUUUAUUUUAUUCCUUAUAGGGGCUUUCACAGCUUUAUGGCUGUUGGAUAUUUAUGUCCCCAAACUUGCAGCAAGUUUGGUGAAGGCCCCUAAAUUUAAUUAAACUUAGGAUUUUUAUACUCUUUUGGCAGAGAAGGCUCUAUAUUAAUAUUCACGUUUGACUGUGGUGUUAAUAAACAUAAGUAUUUCAUAUGCAAUUUUAUGUAAUUUGCUGUGUGUUACAUAAUUAACAGCUUCAGUAAAGCUUGUGUUCCUAUAUUGAACUUCAAUAAAUUGACAAAAUUUGAUAUUUUUGAUUGGAGGCAAGAAAUGUUUCAUUCAAGUUUUUUACUUUCACUUCUAGGAAAAUCUUACUGGUUUUAUUUUCUCCAUAAACUAUUAAAUUUAACCUCAAGGAUAAGUUUAAUCAUUGGAAAUGCCACUGGAUACUGAAAUGUGCCUUCUCUUUUUUGAGACGGAGUUUCACUCUUAUCACCCAGGAUGGAGUGCAGUGGUGCGAUCUCGGUUCACUGCAACCUCUGCCUCCCGGAUUCAAGUGAUUCUCCUGCCUCAGCCUCCCGAGUAGCUGGGAUUAUAGGCUCCCGCCACCACAUCUGGCUAUUUUUUCAAUAUUUUUCAGUAGGGAUGGGGUUUUGCCGUGUUGGCCAGGCUGGUCUCAAACUCCUGACCUCAGGUGAUCCACCCAUCUCAGCCUCCCAGAGUGCUGGAGUAGCAGGUGUGAGCCACCGCGCCUGGCCAAAAUCUGCAUUCUUUUUUUUUUUUUUUUUUUUUUUUUGAGACUGUCUCGCUGUGUCACCCAGGCCAGAGUGCAGUAGCACGAUCUCAGCUCACUACAACCUCCACCUCCUGGAUUCAAGCGAUUCUCCUGUCUCAGCCUCCCGAGUAGCUGGGACUACAGGUGCUUGCCACCACACCCGGCUAAUUUUUUGUAUUUUUAGUAGAGACGGGGUUUCACCGUGUUAGCCAGGAUGGUCUCGAUCUCCUGACUUUGCGAUCCCCCUGCCUCGGCCUCCCAAAGUGCUGGGAUUACAGGCGUGGGCCACCGCGCUUGGCCAAAAUCUGCAUUCUUAAUCACAAACUUACGCAUUGAAUGUUAAGGCUAAAAGGUCAUCUGGAAAUGCUUAAUUUUAAAAUAUUUUCAAGCCUCACCACAUUAGAGCAAAUGUUAAUGUAGAGCCCUGUAAAGGUGGGAAGGUGGUGUCUAUGUGUGUGCUUGUGUAUGUGGGGGUAUAGACCAUAUAGUUGAUAUAACAACAGAAUUUGGGUGUUACAGACCUUUCAGCAUGGAUGGAUUACUAAUUUUCAGGUAUCGAAACUGAAAUUUGAUACCUGAUCCUGUGGUAAAGUAUGUUAAACUAUGGUUUUGGAGUGAUUAUUUUGAGGUUCAUUUUCAGCCUCACUGAACAGUGUUUUACGCACAUGUGAAAAGUAUCCACAUUUGUUUCCAACUAAAAUUUGCUUUUAUUUGGUGAGAAAAGUUGUGUGCGUGUGUUUGUUGUAGGGAAUAAUUAGGGAAUUGGAAGAGAGGCCAAAAACAAACCUGAAUUACUUUUGUUUCUUGUGUUUGAGCCACGAUUCUAUCCAGAUAGCAGUUUACUCUGAGCAGUAACAAUGAACAAGCAGUAUAGCAUUUAGCAAACCUGGAAUUGUUUGUAUAUGGUUUUCAUUCUUGGAAGCAUAAAGAAAAAAUAUGCAUUAAAUGAAUUGUAAAUUUUGACUUGUUAAAUAACAUGUUUUUCACUAUAACUAAUAGGAUUUUAAUAUUUAAAGAAUUUUGUUGCUUCCAUGACAAAAUAUCCCAUUGGACUAUUUUAUAACCUCAGUAAUCAACAUUUAAGAGUCCUUAAUUGGAGAUCUGUUUUCUCUAUUACCUACCAUCCUGCAAUAUGCUGAAAUCUUUCUAAGUUGCUUAUCUUAAUUCUAAUGGUGAUAAUUGAAAAAAGUGUGCUGGAAAUACAGGCUCUUAUCUGGUUGAGUACUGGGGGUGGGAAGGAUUUAGUAAUGUCAUAAUCUGUUGAAGGUAAUAUCUAUAGAUAACUAAGAUAGUUCCUUUUUUUUUGUAGUUCUGUGACUCAGACAAAUAAGAUUUUGAGAAUUAUGUAGUUUUUAGGUGUCUGUAACAUCCACUAGUAAAACUUGGCAAAUGAAAGAAAAUUGUGAAGUCACCACUUUAACUGAGUCAAAAUUUUGUUUGAAUAAGCUGAUGAAAAUAGACAUGUACCCUAGAAGUAGAUACUCUAAAAUUAUACAGACAUGAAUGUCUUUUUUAAAAGGUUGUCAUUAUUGACCUAAUAUUGAGUAAUCUUUCUGCGUUAUUCCAAAUUGAAAUUUGUUUGCUCUUCAUUGUAACUUUUAUGUAAAAGUCCUUUAAAAGGGGAUUCAAUUAUAAGGCUAUUUGACUAUAGGGCAGAUUUUUAUAAGUAAACAUUCCCCCAAUUCCACUUAUGCUAACUGUCUCAUGACAGUAAAGUUUACUCCUUUUUAGAAACCCUUUCUCAGUAUUUUAAUUUCUGUCAUUGAAUCAUUUAAAUAAUAACCUUUUGUUUUUAUAGCAAAGAAAUCAUCUGACUUUUCUGUGUGAUGUUUCUUGGCAAAAUAAGCACUUGAUGUAUGGUCAUGUACAUAAUGGAUAUUCAUUAAUUUUGUGAUUAGUGCUGAGUUUUCUAAACUACUAUCUUAAGCUCUUAGGCACCCUAUUAUGGAUCUAAUUCAAACCAAUAUGUAGGAAAUGGAGAAAGUAGGACUUCAGUUUGCGCUUCCCAAUAACUUUAAAUAUAUCCACCUUUUCCAAGUGUUUAAGCCCUAAAACAUCUAUCUUUAUUUUUUUACCUGGCAUUUUUGUUAGAAAAUAGAUUACGUUUUAAAGUAACAUUAAAAAAAUUCUUCAGUAAGAUAAUUGCUUUUAAUAAGUAUAUUUUUCUUGCUCUUGGCUCUAUACAUUUUUGCAUAAUAUUUUAGUCUUGAAAAGCUUUUCAUUUUCUUAACUCUGGAAAAUAAUAGUUUGGAACUAAAUUAGUUUGAGAAAUCUGAAUCAUCUCUCUUUAAAUCUGUUCAGUUAGUCUCAUGUAUUCUCAGGGGAAAAUGUCUUUAUUUUACUAAGCGGAAGUAGUAGUCAUAUUGAGGCAGAAAUUUGUAGCCCAAACAAGGUAGGUCUUCGCUGAAACUAAUUUGAACUAUUCCUAUUUGAAGCAAAUUGAACACUAUUAUAAAUCUAGACUGGCUAAUUAGAUGGAAACUUUGAUGGUUAGGUUCUUUAAGAGGCAUACAAUCCGUUAUGAGAAUGUUUAUGUUUAUGUUUUAAUUUUUAUCAAAAUAACCUCAGAGGAGGUACAUGUGAGUAAACUGUCUUAAUGGUUGAUUACUUGGAACCCACCCAUUAAUUCUAAAUGAUGUAAUGGUCUAUAAGGUAGUAAUCUGGCACAGCUUCAGUAAUGUGUGCUGUGUUUGUAAAAAGGUGAAGUACUUUAUUGGCAUUUUCUAAGCCCUCUGACAUUGUUAGUGUCUGGGUUGGUUGGUUUGCAUUUUACUAUUAUGGUGGAAUCUGUGUUCCUUCACCAUUGGUUAAGUCUGAGGAACUAACAGUGAAAUUCAUUGAUGGCCAACUUGGAUAAAAAUGAAGAAUGAUAUUUUCCCAGUUUACUACACAUGGACCAAUAGUGAUUAUUUGGGAGAGAACACUGGGUAGUAUUGUUUGACUUAAGAACCUUAAAUAUAUUGAAAAGUAAUGGCAUUCUUGCUCAUGAUUUGCAUUUGUUAGUGAGGUCUCACCAUAGUAUUUUAAUGUAGCUUCUUAUUAAAAUUUUAUUCAUAAAUAGUUUAGCAGUCACAGAGGUGAAAAAAAAAAGAUUUGCACCAUCAUAUCCGAGUCUUUACUAAUAAAAUGAGGCUGCUUAAGUACCCAAGUGGAGCAAGGGAAGAGUUACUACAGUUACUGUAAGUCUGAGUUAGAAAAAAUACAGAGCAUCUAGUUAUUGAGCAAAGCCCCCUUUUACCUGUUCGCUUAUUCAAAGAGAAACAAUAGAAUUUGCUUCUCAGUACAUGUUUUUAAAAUUGAGAAUCUCUGAUGUGACAAAAUCAAUUUUUACAAAAGUUGAAUUAAAAACUUUUAAAAAUUGCUUGUCUUUGGGGGUAUGUCUACAUAUUCGUUUAAAUUUAGAAAUUCCCACAUGUUUAAGAUAUAUGCCCAUCCCCUUUUUAGAGUAAUCAAAAUUUCUAUCACAGUUCACAUACUGGAAUACAUAGUAAAAUUGAGAUGUGUCCAAGAGAUUUUCAAUGUUAAUUAGCUCAUUCUAAAUAGCCAAUAUAAGGUAACUUCUGUUUAAAAAAAAAAAAAACUAGGGAAAAGUUUUAAAUGUAUUAGUAUCAGGCUCUGAGGAAAUUUAAUGCACAUUGACUUUUUAAACUAUGGAUUGAACUCCUCAGUUUAAUACAAUUUGUGUUUUUGUUAACUAGCAGCAGAAUUUCAGCAUUUGCUACUUACUGGUAGAGAAGAAAAAUCCCACAGCCCUGCCAGUACAGGUUAGUUUAAUCUGUAAGUACCUGAUGUUCCUAUUUUUUUCAAACAUAUCCAUAUAACUCACACAAGGAAGAAAGCUGUGCGGUUACUUAAAUGUUAGUAUAACUAAUAAUAGAUCCAUUGGACACUUUAAACACUCAGUACUUGGGCCAAAGUAGAUCUAGGUUUGCUAACCCCAGUUGUAAUAAAGGUGUAAUACUGCUCCUUUGUUAUCUCCUUGUGGUUCAACCUAAGUAGAUACAUUGUACAUAAAAGGAAAAGACAGUUUCAGUUGGCUAUGCCCUUGUUGAUAGAUGAUAUGGAGUCCAGGGCUUUGGGUCCAGGGUCUUUUACUUAAGCUAUUUCAUGGUGGUUCUCUCAUUCACCUUUUAACUUUUUACAUUAUGAAUCAACCUAAGAAAAAAGGCAAGUUUCCUCACAUCUAGAAAUGAUAAAUGGUGUACAGUCAUAAGCUAGAAUAUGUUUUUAUAAUGCUUUUUUGUUCUUUUAGCAACACUUGUAAAUACAAGUACUCCUCUAUUUUUGUUCUUUUUUUGUAAACUAUAACGUAUCCCGUUGGUGUACCAGUGAGUUCAUUUUACUGUAAACUAAGAAUAACAUACCUUUUUAAUACUGAAAGUUGACUACUCAUCAAGAAAUGUAGCUAGAUUCUUUAUGUAACACUUUUGAGGGGCAGUGGGGACAUAAUGGGUUGUGGAAAAUGUGUUUUAACAUUUUUAUUUUUUUUUUAUUCUACCCGAGUUCAUUGUUGUUUGAACCAUCCUCUAAAGAUUUCCUUUAACCUCUAAAUGUUGUGCUUUUAGGUUGAUAACAAAUGUAAAGCACUGAGGAGGGAGGAAUAAAGCAUACAAGUUAAUUUCUAAUUUUCGCAAGCCUGAACCAUCCUAAUCUGAUAGUAGGAUGUAUGGCUUCUUCCUUUUCACCUUGUGUGAUGUUUAAUUUGAGACGAUCUAGCCAUAAAACUAGUAAUCUUGAAUUCCUCUUGAGCUGGAUGGUGAUUAGCCAUUGUGAAAACAGAUUAUAUGGAAAUUGUGCAUAUUGCUAAAUUUUAAAACAUGGAUUUAUCAACUGAUAAUAAAAUAUAUCUUACAAGAUAACCACUUGUUUUUUAAUGUAAAAUUGCACAAGGGCUUAAGUUUCAUUGCCUUUCACAGUUUAAUCUGUAUAUGAAAUGGUGUAGAUACAGUGGAAAUGGUUUUCCUUAAAACCAUCUCUUUAAAGCUGCCUUUCUGGUGAGUACUGUUUUAUACUUUUAUAUAUUAUAAUUUUAUCUUCUAAAAUUAACUGAAAUAGGACACUUUGAUUAAAGAGGUGAGCACUCUGAAUUUCUACAUCUUUGGAUAUUACUUGAAUCAAGAAUAUUAGAAAAUUAUUUUACCACCUGGCAUUUCCCUUUUAAUUUGCUAGUUCACUUUUUUCUGACCUUCACUUAACAGACUAUAAAUACAAAAACUUUGAACACAUAAAUUAUUUCAUUUUGGUGAGAUGGAAUAAAUGUUUAAAAUUAGUAUUUAAGAAAGUUCUUAAACAUUUUUUUUAGUUGGCAGCCAAAAGAUUUUUCUUAGUGCUUUGGAGACAUUGCAUAGGUGUAAAAUUAAGAUACCAGAACUUCAUUCUGUUCUUGUUGAAGCUGUUGUUGUGGUGAUUCAUGAGCAGUAAGCUGGAGUUAGAGUGGAAGAAGGGUUUACCAAAAUUCUUCCUGCAGACUAGUUGCUUACAGGGUUUCUUUGAGAGGCUUAAAAAUUUCAAAAGUAUUAUUUAAGCCACUCUAACCCUGCAUGAAAAAUUGGAGUUAGAAAUACUGAUUUCUGAGACCACGUAUACCAGUGAAAAUUAGCUUCUGAGUAAAUUUCUAAUUUAUGCCCUGCUUUAUUUAGCCUCGCUAUAUGUAACACAUGGAUUAUUUUUUCCCUCUAGUUUUUAACUAUAUCCUAGAUUAAAACCAGCAUAUGCUAAGAAUGUUUUUACAUUCUGUUUCCUCCUGUGAUCUUUCUGAACCAAUAAUAAACAGUCAACUGUGAUGCUUUUUAGUAUGAACAAUGAUAGUUUUCUAAAAUCUGAAAAUCAAUACCUGAGUAUGUGAUGUGGCAAUGCAUUCUUCUAGAUAAGCACUAAACAAAGUAUGGACCCUCAAUUUAUGUCUUUAAGAUUUAAAGUGAAGUAAAUUUCUAAGGAACUGUGUCCUUUCCUAGCAGGAAUAAACAGUGAAAAUUUGGUAAGUAUUUAACUUGAAGUGCAUGUAAUAGUGAUGAGAGUAAGUAGCCAAAUUUCCGUAAUAUAAGGUAAUGUUUAAAAGUGAGCAAUAAUUAUUGCAUCUCUUUUGCGACUUCAUGUAGAUGUGAUUAACAUUUUUUACAAAUUUGCCUGCAUAAAGAUUAAAUUGGAACAUACCUUACUCCUUUGUCUGGUUUUUUUAUUUUGUAUGGUGCUUUAAAUACUAAUUUUAUAUUUCAAGCUUUUUGCAGGGUAGAAAUAAGUGGCUGUUAAAGAAAAUAUCUUCAAGAAGGAUUAUUUCAGUGUCCCUUUUUAAAACUCGAUGAUGGCUUUCAGUUUAUUUAAGUCUUCUGUUUUUCAGCUCCAGUUAAAACUGACAAUAGGCAGCUAUCAAAAAUGGAAAAAAUCUUGUGCUCUUUCUGGAAUAUUAGAGGAAUCAGUUAAUAAUAGUAAAGUGGUAUUAACCCAAUACUUGAUUUGCAGUUUUUAAAGCAGUUUUUAAAUUGAGAGAAAAGGGGCUGGGCCCAGCUGAGGCGGGUGGAUCUCCUGAGGUCAGGAGUUUGAGACCAGCCUGGCCAACAUAGUGAAACCCCGUCUCUACUAAAAAUACAAAAAUCAGCCGGGUGUGGUGGGACGUGCCUGUAACCCCAGCUACUCUGGAGGCUGAGGCAGGAAAAUCGCUUGAACCCAGGGGGAGGAGGUUGCAGUGAGCCGAGAUGGCGCCGUUGCACUCCAGCUUGGGUGACAGAGCGAGACUCCGUCUCAAAAAAAAAAAGAAAAAAAGAAAAAGUGAUAAGAUUUGGGAGUCUAUUCCCUGGGAUGUUCUAUUAAUAAUAAAGUGAUAAUAAAUGAAGGUUAAAGUCAAGUGUUCAAUUACUACACCAGGAAAGAUUGAUUAUUUCUGAGGAAAAGGUCCAUUUAUUUCCAAACUAGUCUGUAGUGGUUUAGAGUAAGCAUUAUUUUAUGAAGUGGUACAAGAUUGCAAAGGUUAGUAAAGGGACCUGUCUGUCAGGUCAAUCUUCGGUCUUCACUUUUACUGGCAAGGGAUUAUGUGAAGAGUAAGUCAUACAAGGGAUAUGAUUGUAAGGAGGUCCUGAACAAAGCAUGAUAAAUGUUAGUCCAUGUGUAUUAUUAAAUGGUCUAAAGAAAAAUCAUGACUGAUCGCAUAAUUUUUAAUGUAAGUAAAUGAGCUCACUAAGGGUAAUUAAAUACUAGCUUUUAAAAUUUAAAGUUCUCACGAAUAUUAGUGCAUCUUGUCACUUUGAUUUGUCACCUGGUUAAAUAGCUGGAAGCUUGUGCAAAUGAAAAAUGAAAUGGAAGACUACAUUUGUAUAUAUAUCUGUAUAAUUUUUGUUUACUAGUAGGUUCAGAGAGAGAUCUGAGAUGUUCCUUAACAUGUAGCCAUGUAAUUAGAACUCACAAGGGGCAUUGAAAUGUUUUUCUUUUUCAGAUAGUCUGGGGCUAUUUACUUAUUUUAAGUAAGCCAAGUCUACCAUUUGAAAAAUGGUGCUUUAUUUCCAUAUCUGAAGCCUGAAGUUAUUUUUUAGUUUGUUUUCAUCUAAAAGUGGAAAGAUUUUUGCUUCUGCGUUAUUAAGAGCCUCUUUGUUUGGAGGAGAUGGUUAUCUCCUUCACUCAUUAACCUUUGAGUGCUUGUUAUCUACAAAGAUGAAUAAAAUCUUUCAUUUAUUAUUUA